AUUAGUAUAACGUGAGGGCUGAAUGCAGCCCAUUCUCUGGAGAACUUCCUCACACACCGCAGCAAAGAGAAGACUGAAAGACAAACCUGGGUGCAGCCAGAGAGGUCCAGAUAGAUGAGCUUGUGGCAUCCAUUCCCCAAGUUCAGGUACUGUAAGCCUUUGUCUGUGAACCGUCUGCAAUAAGCCAAACUAAGAUUCUGUAAGUUGUGGAAGUGCCUGAAAAGACAAAAGAGAGGAAGGAAAGUAUUAUACUUCCGUUGUUCUCUCAAAUCUUUCUUAAGCCACUAUGACAAAGAAAACUGUAAAUUCAACUCUUCUUCUUGCAGAUGUUCAACAUUUAACUUUACUGUUAACUCUCUACCUGUUAAUUAAAGGAGACUACAGUGUUAUAUAAGAUGGUGGUAAGUGCCAUGGAGAAGAAAGAAGAAAAGGGAUUGGGAGCACCCAACAAGUGGGAAGAAGUGUGAUUUAAAAUAGGGCUGAACAGGAAGUUUUCACUGAAAAGGUAACAUUUGAGCCAAGACAUGCAGGAGAUGACAAGGACAGUGCCAUUUACUCCAAGCAUCUCUGGAGCCCACACCCAACAUGGUUGGUGACUGGGAGACAGAAAAGGAUAGAAAAAAAAAAGGCUCAGGAAGACAACAAUUCAAGUCCUACCCUUGUGUGUGCAUCUCAAGGCUGUGUUCUUUUAAAGAAGGAGAAUUCUUUGAAUUUCUUAAAUCCGAUGUGAUGGUGAACUGCAGGCUUCGGUUUUCAUCAUGCUGAGUCCUAACAUUUGUGACUACUUCCCCCGGGGUGGCCAUGUGAAGCAUCUUAUGCGCAUGAGCCUAUUUUAUCCUCCCAACAAUAUUAGGAGGUAUCCUCGGUCCGUUUUACAGAUGCUGAAGAUGACCCAGGUUGAUACAGUUAAGCAGCCUAGGGACUCCACGUACCCCAGCUGGGUCUCAUUGUUCCAGAACUGCAUUAGUUAAGAUUACCCAGACUUGGAUUUCAAAGGAAUACUUUCAUUGUUCCGUCUGUAACACGAAGUAAUUGGGGCCAGCUGGAUGUCAGGAUGCGUGUGGUUACCAUUGUAAUCUUGCUCUGCUUUUGCAAAGCGGCUGAGCUGCGCAAAGCAAGCCCAGGCAGUGUGAGAAGCCGAGUGAAUCAUGGCCGGGCGGGUGGAGGCCGGAGAGGCUCCAACCCGGUCAAACGCUACGCACCAGGCCUCCCGUGUGACGUGUACACAUAUCUCCAUGAGAAAUACUUAGAUUGUCAAGAAAGAAAAUUAGUUUAUGUGCUGCCUGGUUGGCCUCAGGAUUUGCUGCACAUGCUGCUAGCAAGAAACAAGAUCCGCACAUUGAAGAACAACAUGUUUUCCAAGUUUAAAAAGCUGAAAAGCCUGGAUCUGCAGCAGAAUGAGAUCUCUAAAAUUGAGAGUGAGGCGUUCUUUGGUUUAAACAAACUCACCACCCUCUUACUGCAGCACAACCAGAUCAAAGUCUUGACGGAGGAAGUGUUCAUUUACACACCUCUCUUGAGCUACCUGCGUCUUUAUGACAACCCCUGGCACUGUACUUGUGAGAUAGAAACGCUUAUUUCAAUGUUGCAGAUUCCCAGGAACCGGAAUUUGGGGAACUACGCCAAGUGUGAAAGUCCACAAGAACAAAAAAAUAAAAAACUGCGGCAGAUAAAAUCUGAACAGUUGUGUAAUGAAGAAGAAAAGGAACAAUUGGACCCGAAACCCCAAGUGUCAGGGAGACCCCCAGUCAUCAAGCCUGAGGUGGACUCAACUUUUUGCCACAAUUAUGUGUUUCCCAUACAAACACUGGACUGCAAAAGGAAAGAGUUGAAAAAAGUGCCAAACAACAUCCCUCCAGAUAUUGUUAAACUUGACUUGUCAUACAAUAAAAUCAACCAACUUCGACCCAAGGAAUUUGAAGAUGUUCAUGAGCUGAAGAAAUUAAACCUCAGCAGCAAUGGCAUUGAAUUCAUCGAUCCUGCCGCUUUUUUAGGGCUCACACAUUUAGAAGAAUUAGAUUUAUCAAACAACAGUCUGCAAAACUUUGACUAUGGCGUAUUAGAAGACUUGUAUUUUUUGAAACUCUUGUGGCUCAGAGAUAACCCUUGGAGAUGUGACUACAACAUUCACUACCUCUACUACUGGUUAAAGCACCACUACAAUGUCCAUUUUAAUGGCCUGGAAUGCAAAACGCCUGAAGAAUACAAAGGAUGGUCUGUGGGAAAAUAUAUUAGAAGUUACUAUGAAGAAUGCCCCAAAGACAAGUUACCAGCAUAUCCUGAGUCAUUUGACCAAGACACAGAAGAUGAUGAAUGGGAAAAAAAACAUAGAGAUCACACCGCAAAGAAGCAAAGCGUAAUAAUUACUAUAGUAGGAUAAGGUAGAAAUUGUUCUGAUUGUAAUUAGUUUUGUAUUUUCUAUACUGGUGUUAGAAAACAUAUGUUUACAUUUGAUUAACUGUGUUGCCUAUUUAUGCAGGGUAAUCCAGCUAAAGGAAGCUUUCUUUAAUUAUAAGUAUUAUUGUGACUAUUAUAGUAAUCAAGAGAAUGCUAUCAUCCUGCUUGCCUGUCCAUUUGUGGAACAGCAUCUGGUGAUAUGCAAUUCCACACUGGUAACCUGCAGCAGUUGGGUCCUAAUGAUGGCAUUAGACUUUCAUAAUGUCCUGUAUAAAUGUUUUUACUGCUUUUAGAAAAUAAAGAAAAAAAACUUGGUUCAUGUUUACAUGCCUUUCGAUAGCUGUUUGUGCAUACUUAAAGAUGAUCAAAAUGAUUUUAUACAAAUGCUGUUAUAAUAAAAUGUCAUUCCCUACCCCUCUACUUUUUUUCAGUAAGUCAUCUUAUACAUUAAAUAAAUUUCCAUUUCUGAUUUCUGUGCAUUCCAAAA